AGUGUAGCUGCGAGAACCUUUGCACGCGCACAAACUACGGGGACGAUUUCUGAUUGAUUUUUGGCGCUUUCGAUCCACCCUCCUCCCUUCUCAUGGGACUUUGGGGACAAAGCGUCCCGACCGCCUCGAGCGCUCGAGCAGGGCGCUAUCCAGGAGCCAGGACAGCGUCGGGAACCAGACCAUGGCUCCUGGACCCCAAGAUCCUUAAGUUCGUCGUCUUCAUCGUCGCGGUUCUGCUGCCGGUCCGGGUUGACUCUGCCACCAUCCCCCGGCAGGACGAAGUUCCCCAGCAGACAGUGGCCCCACAGCAACAGAGGCGCAGCCUCAAGGAGGAGGAGUGUCCAGCAGGAUCUCAUAGAUCAGAAUAUACUGGAGCCUGUAACCCGUGCACAGAGGGUGUGGAUUACACCAUUGCUUCCAACAAUUUGCCUUCUUGCCUGCUAUGUACAGUUUGUAAAUCAGGUCAAACAAAUAAAAGUUCCUGUACCACGACCAGAGACACCGUGUGUCAGUGUGAAAAAGGAAGCUUCCAGGAUAAAAACUCCCCUGAGAUGUGCCGGACGUGUAGAACAGGGUGUCCCAGAGGGAUGGUCAAGGUCAGUAAUUGUACGCCCCGGAGUGACAUCAAGUGCAAAAAUGAAUCAGCUGCCAGUUCCACUGGGAAAACCCCAGCAGCGGAGGAGACAGUGACCACCAUCCUGGGGAUGCUUGCCUCUCCCUAUCACUACCUUAUCAUCAUAGUGGUUUUAGUCAUCAUUUUAGCUGUGGUUGUGGUUGGCUUUUCAUGUCGGAAGAAAUUCAUUUCUUACCUCAAAGGCAUCUGCUCAGGUGGUGGAGGAGGUCCCGAACGUGUGCACAGAGUCCUUUUCCGGCGGCGUUCAUGUCCUUCACGAGUUCCUGGGGCGGAGGACAAUGCCCGCAACGAGACCCUGAGUAACAGAUACUUGCAGCCCACCCAGGUCUCUGAGCAGGAAAUCCAAGGUCAGGAGCUGGCAGAGCUAACAGGUGUGACUGUAGAGUUGCCAGAGGAGCCACAGCGUCUGCUGGAACAGGCAGAAGCUGAAGGGUGUCAGAGGAGGAGGCUGCUGGUUCCAGUGAAUGACGCUGACUCCGCUGACAUCAGCACCUUGCUGGAUGCCUCGGCAACACUGGAAGAAGGACAUGCAAAGGAAACAAUUCAGGACCAACUGGUGGGCUCCGAAAAGCUCUUUUAUGAAGAAGAUGAGGCAGGCUCUGCUACGUCCUGCCUGUGAAAGAAUCUCUUCAGGAAACCAGAGCUUCCCUCAUUUACCUUUUCUCCUACAAAGGGAAGCAGCCUGGAAGAAACAGUCCAGUACUUGACCCAUGCCCCAACAAACUCUACUAUCCAAUAUGGGGCAGCUUACCAAUGGUCCUAGAACUUUGUUAACGCACUUGGAGUAAUUUUUAUGAAAUACUGCGUGUGAUAAGCAAACGGGAGAAAUUUAUAUCAGAUUCUUGGCUGCAUAGUUAUACGAUUGUGUAUUAAGGGUCGUUUUAGGCCACAUGCGGUGGCUCAUGCCUGUAAUCCCAGCACUUUGAUAGGCUGAGGCAGGUGGAUUGCUUGAGCUCGGGAGUUUGAGACCAGCCUCAUCAACACAGUGAAACUCCAUCUCAAUUUAAAAAGAAAAAAAGUGGUUUUAGGAUGUCAUUCUUUGCAGUUCUUCAUCAUGAGACAAGUCUUUUUUUCUGCUUCUUAUAUUGCAAGCUCCAUCUCUACUGGUGUGUGCAUUUAAUGACAUCUAACUACAGAUGCCGCACAGCCACAAUGCUUUGCCUUAUAGUUUUUUAACUUUAGAACGGGAUUAUCUUGUUAUUACCUGUAUUUUCAGUUUCGGAUAUUUUUGACUUAAUGAUGAGAUUAUCAAGACGUAGCCCUAUGCUAAGUCAUGAGCAUAUGGACUUACGAGGGUUCGACUUAGAGUUUUGAGCUUUAAGAUAGGAUUAUUGGGGCUUACCCCCACCUUAAUUAGAGAAACAUUUAUAUUGCUUACUACUGUAGGCUGUACAUCUCUUUUCCGAUUUUUGUAUAAUGAUGUAAACAUGGAAAAACUUUAGGAAAUGCACUUAUUAGGCUGUUUACAUGGGUUGCCUGGAUACAAAUCAGCAGUCAAAAAUGACUAAAAAUAUAACUAGUGACGGAGGGAGAAAUCCUCCCUCUGUGGGAGGCACUUACUGCAUUCCAGUUCUCCCUCCUGCGCCCUGAGACUGGACCAGGGUUUGAUGGCUGGCAGCUUCUCAAGGGGCAGCUUGUCUUACUUGUUAAUUUUAGAGGUAUAUAGCCAUAUUUAUUUAUAAAUAAAUAUUUAUUUAUUUAUUUAUAAGUAGAUGUUUACAUAUGCCCAGGAUUUUGAAGAGCCUGGUAUCUUUGGGAAGCCAUGUGUCUGGUUUGUCGUGCUGGGACAGUCAUGGGACUGCAUCUUCCGACUUGUCCACAGCAGAUGAGGACAGUGAGAAUUAAGUUAGAUCCGAGACUGCGAAGAGCUUCUCUUUCAAGCGCCAUUACAGUUGAACGUUAGUGAAUCUUGAGCCUCAUUUGGGCUCAGGGCAGAGCAGGUGUUUAUCUGCCCCGGCAUCUGCCAUGGCAUCAAGAGGGAAGAGUGGACGGUGCUUGGGAAUGGUGUGAAAUGGUUGCCGACUCAGGCAUGGAUGGGCCCCUCUCGCUUCUGGUGGUCUGUGAACUGAGUCCCUGGGAUGCCUUUUAGGGCAGAGAUUCCUGAGCUGCGUUUUAGGGUACAGAUUCCCUGUUUGAGGAGCUUGGCCCCUCUGUAAGCAUCUGACUCAUCUCAGAGAUAUCAAUUCUUAAACACUGUGACAACAGGAUCUAAAAUGGCUGACACAUUUGUCCUUGUGUCACGUUCCAUUAUUUUAUUUAAAAACCUCAGUAAUCGUUUUAGCUUCUUUCCAGCAAACUCUUCUCCACAGUAGCCCAGUCGUGGUAGGAUAAAUUACGGAUAUAGUCAUUCUAGGGGUUUCAGUCUUUUCCAUCUCAAGGCAUUGUGUGUUUUGUUCCGGGACUGGUUUGGCUGGGACAAAGUUAGAACUGCCUGAAGUUCGCACAUUCAGAUUGUUGUGUCCAUGGAGUUUUAGGAGGGGAUGGCCUUUCCGGUCUUCGCACUUCCAUCCUCUCCCACUUCCAUCUGGCGUCCCACACCUUGUCCCCUGCACUUCUGGAUGACACAGGGUGCUGCUGCCUCCUAGUCUUUGCCUUUGCUGGGCCUUCUGUGCAGGAGACUUGGUCUCAAAGCUCAGAGAGAGCCAGUCCGGUCCCAGCUCCUUUGUCCCUUCCUCAGAGGCCUUCCUUGAAGAUGCAUCUAGACUACCAGCCUUAUCAGUGUUUAAGCUUAUUCCUUUAACAUAAGCUUCCUGACAACAUGAAAUUGUUGGGGUUUUUUGGCGUUGGUUGAUUUGUUUAGGUUUUGCUUUAUACCCGGGCCAAAUAGCACAUAACACCUGGUUAUAUAUGAAAUACUCAUAUGUUUAUGACCAAAAUAAAUAUGAAACCUCAUAUUAAAAA